CUCUCUUCCCCCCGCCCUGCCUUCCCUUGCACCCUCCUUCUUCCCUCCGCCCGGGAGCUCUCCCUGGUCCCCGGCGCCGCCUCCUUCCCUCCCGGCUCCCCGCUCCCCGCUCCCGUGGCUGCCGCCGCCCCGGGGAAGAAGAGACAGGGGUGGGGUUUGGGGGAAGCGAGAGAGGAGGGGAGAGACCCUGGCCAGGCUGGAGCCUGGAUUCGAGGGGAGGAGGGACGGGAGGAGGAGAAAGGUGGAGGAGAAGGGAGGGGGGAGCGGGGAGGAGCGGCCGGGCCUGGGGCCUUGAGGCCCGGGGAGAGCCGGGGAGCCGGGCCCGCGCGCCGAGGCUGAGCCCGGUCGGAGCCUGCGAGGCAACCGGCAAGAGGUCGAGUAGUCUCCGGGUGCGGGCCGCGCCGGCGGGGCUCGGUCCAGUCCUCAUGGCCGCCUCUCACUUAGAUGUUGCUGCUGCUGCUACUGGCGCCACUCUUCCUCCGCCCCCCGGGCGCGGGCGGGGUGCAGACCCCCAACGCCACCUCAGAAGGUUGCCAGAUCAUACACCCGCCCUGGGAAGGGGGCAUCAGGUACCGGGGCCUGACUCGGGACCAGGUGAAGGCUAUCAACUUCCUGCCAGUGGACUAUGAGAUUGAGUAUGUGUGCCGGGGGGAGCGCGAGGUGGUGGGGCCCAAGGUCCGCAAGUGCCUGGCCAACGGCUCCUGGACAGAUAUGGACACACCCAGCCGCUGUGUCCGAAUCUGCUCCAAGUCUUAUUUGACCCUGGAAAAUGGGAAGGUUUUCCUGACGGGUGGGGACCUCCCAGCUCUGGACGGAGCCCGGGUGGAUUUCCGGUGUGACCCCGACUUCCAUCUGGUGGGCAGCUCCCGGAGCAUCUGUAGUCAGGGCCAGUGGAGCACCCCCAAGCCCCACUGCCAGGUGAAUCGAACGCCACACUCAGAACGGCGCGCAGUGUACAUCGGGGCACUGUUUCCCAUGAGCGGGGGCUGGCCAGGGGGCCAGGCCUGCCAGCCCGCGGUGGAGAUGGCGCUGGAGGACGUGAAUAGCCGCAGGGACAUCCUGCCGGACUAUGAGCUCAAGCUCAUCCACCACGACAGCAAGUGUGAUCCAGGCCAAGCCACCAAGUACCUAUAUGAGCUGCUCUACAACGACCCUAUCAAGAUCAUCCUUAUGCCUGGCUGCAGCUCUGUCUCCACGCUGGUGGCUGAGGCUGCUAGGAUGUGGAACCUCAUUGUGCUUUCCUAUGGCUCCAGCUCACCAGCCCUGUCAAACCGGCAGCGUUUCCCCACUUUCUUCCGAACGCACCCAUCAGCCACACUCCACAACCCUACCCGCGUGAAACUCUUUGAAAAGUGGGGCUGGAAGAAGAUUGCUACCAUCCAGCAGACCACUGAGGUCUUCACUUCGACUCUGGACGACCUGGAGGAACGAGUGAAGGAGGCUGGAAUUGAGAUUACUUUCCGCCAGAGUUUCUUCUCAGAUCCAGCUGUGCCCGUCAAAAACCUGAAGCGCCAGGAUGCCCGAAUCAUCGUGGGACUUUUCUAUGAGACUGAAGCCCGGAAAGUUUUUUGUGAGGUGUACAAGGAGCGUCUCUUUGGGAAGAAGUACGUCUGGUUCCUCAUUGGGUGGUAUGCUGACAAUUGGUUCAAGAUCUACGACCCUUCUAUCAACUGCACAGUGGAUGAGAUGACUGAGGCGGUGGAGGGCCACAUCACAACUGAGAUUGUCAUGCUGAAUCCUGCCAAUACCCGCAGCAUUUCCAACAUGACAUCCCAGGAAUUUGUGGAGAAACUAACCAAGCGACUGAAAAGACACCCUGAGGAGACAGGAGGCUUCCAGGAGGCACCGCUGGCCUAUGAUGCCAUCUGGGCCUUGGCACUGGCCCUGAACAAGACAUCUGGAGGAGGCGGCCGUUCCGGCGUGCGCCUGGAGGACUUCAACUACAACAACCAGACCAUUACCGACCAAAUCUACCGGGCAAUGAACUCCUCGUCCUUUGAGGGUGUCUCUGGCCAUGUGGUGUUUGAUGCCAGCGGCUCUCGGAUGGCAUGGACGCUUAUCGAGCAGCUUCAGGGUGGCAGCUACAAGAAGAUUGGCUACUAUGACAGCACCAAGGAUGAUCUUUCCUGGUCCAAAACAGAUAAAUGGAUUGGAGGGUCCCCCCCAGCUGACCAGACCCUGGUCAUCAAGACAUUCCGCUUCCUGUCACAGAAACUCUUUAUCUCCGUCUCAGUUCUCUCCAGCCUGGGCAUUGUCCUAGCUGUUGUCUGUCUGUCCUUUAACAUCUACAACUCACAUGUCCGUUAUAUCCAGAACUCACAGCCCAACCUGAACAACCUGACUGCUGUGGGCUGCUCACUGGCUUUAGCUGCUGUCUUCCCCCUGGGGCUCGAUGGUUACCACAUUGGGAGGAACCAGUUCCCUUUCGUCUGCCAGGCCCGCCUCUGGCUCCUGGGCCUGGGCUUUAGUCUGGGCUACGGUUCCAUGUUCACCAAGAUUUGGUGGGUCCACACGGUCUUCACAAAGAAGGAAGAAAAGAAGGAGUGGAGGAAGACUCUGGAACCCUGGAAGCUGUAUGCCACAGUGGGCCUGCUGGUGGGCAUGGAUGUCCUCACUCUCGCCAUCUGGCAGAUCGUGGACCCUCUGCACCGGACCAUUGAGACAUUUGCCAAGGAGGAACCUAAGGAAGAUAUUGACGUCUCUAUUCUGCCCCAGCUGGAGCAUUGCAGCUCCAGGAAGAUGAAUACAUGGCUUGGCAUUUUCUAUGGUUACAAGGGGCUGCUGCUGCUGCUGGGAAUCUUCCUUGCUUAUGAGACCAAGAGUGUGUCCACUGAGAAGAUCAAUGAUCACCGGGCUGUGGGCAUGGCUAUCUACAAUGUGGCAGUCCUGUGCCUCAUCACUGCUCCUGUCACCAUGAUUCUGUCCAGCCAGCAGGAUGCAGCCUUUGCCUUUGCCUCUCUUGCCAUAGUUUUCUCCUCCUAUAUCACUCUUGUUGUGCUCUUUGUGCCCAAGAUGCGCAGGCUGAUCACCCGAGGGGAAUGGCAGUCGGAGGCGCAGGACACCAUGAAGACAGGGUCAUCGACCAACAACAACGAGGAGGAGAAGUCCCGGCUGUUGGAGAAGGAGAACCGUGAACUGGAAAAGAUCAUUGCUGAGAAAGAGGAGCGUGUCUCUGAACUGCGCCAUCAACUCCAGUCUCGGCAGCAGCUCCGCUCCCGGCGCCACCCACCGACACCCCCAGAACCCUCUGGGGGCCUGCCCAGGGGACCCCCUGAGCCCCCCGACCGGCUUAGCUGUGAUGGGAGUCGAGUGCAUUUGCUUUAUAAGUGAGGGUAGGGUGAGGGAGGACAGGCCAGUAGGGGGAGGGAAAGGGAGAGGGGAAGGGCAGGGGACUCAGGAAGCAGGGGGUCCCCAUCCCCAGCUGGGAAGAACAUGCUAUCCAAUCUCAUCUCUUGUAAAUACAUGUCCCCCUGUGAGUUCUGGGCUGAUUUGGGUCUCUCAUACCUCUGGGAAACAGACCUUUUUCUCUCUUACUGCUUCAUGUAAUUUUGUAUCACCUCUUCACAAUUUAGUUCGUACCUGGCUUGAAGCUGCUCACUGCUCACACGCUGCCUCCUCAGCAGCCUCACUGCAUCUUUCUCUUCCCAUGCAACACCCUCUUCUAGUUACCACGGCAACCCCUGCAGCUCCUCUGCCUUUGUGCUCUGUUCCUGUCCAGCAGGGGUCUCCCAACAAGUGCUCUUUCCACCCCAAAGGGGCCUCUCCUUUUCUCCACUGUCAUAAUCUCUUUCCAUCUUACUUGCCCUUCUAUACUUUCUCACAUGUGGCUCCCCCUGAAUUUUGCUUCCUUUGGGAGCUCAUUCUUUUCGCCAAGGCUCACAUGCUCCUUGCCUCUGCUCUGUGCACUCACGCUCAGCACACAUGCAUCCUCCCCUCUCCUGCGUGUGCCCACUGAACAUGCUCAUGUGUACACACGCUUUUCCCAUAUGCUUUCUUCAUGUUCAGUCACAUGUGCUCUCGGGUGCCCUGCAUUCACAGCUACGUGUGCCCCUCUCAUGGUCAUGGGUCUGCCCUUGAGCGUGUUUGGGUAGGCAUGUGCAAUUUGUCUAGCAUGCUGAGUCAUGUCUUUCCUAUUUGCACACGUCCAUGUUUAUCCAUGUACUUUCCCUGUGUACCCUCCAUGUACCUUGUGUACUUUCUUCCCUUAAAUCAUGGUAUUCUUCUGACAGAGCCAUAUGUACCCUACCCUGCACAUUGUUAUGCACUUUUCCCCAAUUCAUGUUUGGUGGGGCCAUCCACACCCUCUCCUUGUCACAGAAUCUCCAUUUCUGCUCAGAUUCCCCCCAUCUCCAUUGCAUUCAUGUACUACCCUCAGUCUACACUCACAAUCAUCUUCUCCCAAGACUGCUCCCUUUUGUUUUGUGUUUUUUUGAGGGGAAUUAAGGAAAAAUAAGUGGGGGCAGGUUUGGAGAGCUGCUUCCAGUGGAUAGUUGAUGAGAAUCCUGACCAAAGGAAGGCACCCUUGACUGUUGGGAUAGACAGAUGGACCUAUGGGGUGGGAGGUGGUGUCCCUUUCACACUGUGGUGUCUCUUGGGGAAGGAUCUCCCCGAAUCUCAAUAAACCAGUGAACAGUG